AGAGGUCACGUGACGCCGCGCGGGCUGCGCGGGCAGUGGUGGGAAGGCUGGCGCGAGGCGUGAGGUGGCGUGAGGCGAAGCUGGAAUCUGCCUCUGUCACGGGGGCUGGUGCCUCACGGGUUUGUGUCCUAGACAGGCGAGUGGAUCCAAGUGGGCGAGAGACAUUUUAAUCUGGAAGAGUCUUGUGAUUUGGGAGACAGGUUUGGUAACCGUUCGUUAUUCAGUAAUAAAUGUCAGGAAGGAUUGCCAGAUUUUUAGGCAGUGGCUCUGUGUGUGUGUGUGUGUGUGUGUGUGUGUGUGUAGUAGUAGUAGUAGUAGCCUGUUCAUUUUUUUUUUUUUUUUUUUUGAGACGAAGUCUCGGUCUGUCGCCCAGGCUGGAGUGCAGUGGCGCGAUCUCGGCUCACUGCAAGCCCCGCCUCCCGGGUUCACGCCAUCCUCCUGCCUCGGCCUCCCGAGUAGCUGGGACUAUAGGCGUCCGCCACCACGCCCGGCUAAUUUUUUGUAUUUUUAGUAGAGACCGGGUUUCAUUGUGUUAGCCAGGAAGGUCUUGAUCUCCUGACCUCGUGAUCCGCCCGCCUCGGCCUCCCAAAGUGCUGGGAUUACAGGCGUGAGCUACCACGCCGGGCCAGCCUGUUCAUCUUUUAUAAUAAAUAGUGUGAAGAAGAAGUAAAAUAUUCACAAGAUGAAGAUUUUUCCAGAAGGGACUUUGAGUCAAAGAUGGCUUUUUAUAUUUGACAAGUCUUGUCAUCUGUAAUGAAGAUCAUUGUGAAACAGAAGAUUGAUUAAAGCCUUGUAACAUUGGACCUAGAUUAGAGAUUUAGAAAAGAAAGUCAAAAUUAGUCACUUUAGUGUUAGUGUUCCCAUUUCAUAAUAUUUAUUCUUUCUUCUAAAUAGAUUUAGGGAGUAGAAAUUAAAAUUCAAUGCUAUACCAAAGGGUAUACUAAUAUUUGUUUGGCUUUUUUUCCCUUUUUGUGAGGGAGAAAAAAGUAGAUAACGAAAAGCUAUAGUCAUUCGUAAUGAAAUAUACUAAACAGAAUUUUAUGAUGUCAGUUCUUGGCAUUAUAAUCUACGUAACUGAUUUAAUUGUGGACAUAUGGGUAUCUGUCAGAUUUUUCCAUGAAGGACAGUAUGUUUUUAGUGCUUUAGCGUUAAGCUUUAUGCUUUUUGGAACACUUGUGGCUCAGUGUUUUAGUUAUUCUUGGUUCAAGGCUGAUUUAAAGAAAGCAGGCCAAGAAAGUCAGCAUUGUUUUCUUCUACUUCAUUGCUUGCAAGGAGGAGUUUUUACAAGGUAUUGGUUUGCCUUAAAAAGGGGUUACCAUGCAGCUUUUAAAUAUGACAGCAAUACUAGUAACUUCGUGGAAGAACAAAUUGAUCUACAUAAAGAAGUUAUAGAUAGAGUGACUGAUUUGAGCAUGCUCAGACUAUUUGAGACCUACCUGGAAGGCUGCCCACAACUUAUUCUUCAACUCUACAUUCUUCUGGAGCAUGGACAAGCGAAUUUCAGUCAGUAUGCGGCCAUCAUGGUCUCUUGCUGUGCUAUUUCUUGGUCAACUGUUGAUUAUCAAGUAGCUUUAAGAAAAUCCUUGCCUGACAAAAAGCUUCUUAAUGGAUUAUGUCCCAAAAUCACAUAUCUCUUUUACAAGUUGUUUACAUUAUUAUCGUGGAUGCUGAGUGUUGUACUUCUACUAUUCUUAAAUGUUAAGAUUGCUUUAUUUCUGUUGUUAUUUCUUUGGUUGUUAGGUAUAAUAUGGGCAUUUAAAAACAACACCCAGUUUUGUACUUGUAUAAGUAUGGAAUUCUUAUAUAGGAUUGUUGUUGGAUUCAUUCUUAUCUUUACAUUUUUUAAUAUUAAGGGACAGAAUACCAAGUGUCCAAUGUCUUGUUAUUAUAUUGUUAGGGUACUGGGCACUUUGGGGAUAUUGACUGUAUUCUGGGUUUGCCCCCUCACUAUUUUUAAUCCAGACUAUUUUAUACCUAUCAGUAUAACUAUAGUUCUUACUCUUCUUCUUGGAAUUCUUUUUCUUAUUGUUUAUUAUGGGAGUUUUCACCCAAACAGAAGUGCAGAAACAAAAUGUGAUGAAAUUGAUGGAAAACCAGUUCUAAGAGAAUGUAGAAUGAGAUAUUUCCUAAUGGAAUAAGCUAUUCAUUUAUGAUAUAUAUUUUCUUAUAUUUUGUUUCAUUGGUUAGUAAAGAAAAUGUGUGUUAUGUGGGUGUGUUGUCUCUUAUUUUUGCCACCUUUAAUUUGAAAUUAGUUCAGUGAAAUAGGAGAUACAUAGUAGUAUUUUAUUUUUAAAAUUAAUUUCUCAUUUGGUUUUGAAGAUCUUGAGUACUCAGAUAUCUUUCUACUGCCUGGUAGAGCUGCCAUCUUGAGCCUGAAAUAUAAGAAAUGGUCUGGUUUUCAUAAUGAGAAGGCUGGAAUUGAGCUUCCCUCCCAUUUUCCUUGUUCCUGAACUAAUACUACUGUACCUGUUAUGGAGGACUGCAAAGGGAAGAGAAAAGCAGAACACUGUAUUAUUUUUUCCUUUAUUGUCUUCAGUGCAUAUAUUUGCAGUUGGGGACAGGUUGAGUAGAGGAAAAGGGAAAGAAGGGAAAGCAGAAAACAAAUUUUUAGCAUCUGCUGUGCUUUCAUCCAUGAAAUCUCCAAUUCAGUAAGUGCAAAAGAGAAUUGGUGUGCAUCUGAGAGGUCUGACAUUUCAUUAUUUACUUAUUUCCUAGCUUUUCUGAAUUAAUGCACUCUUAACAUAUAAUUAUAUUAAUCCUAUUUGUGCUAGAAUAGUUGUAUCUAAAUCAUAUUUUAAAAUUAUUUUUAUUUUUAAAAAAUUAUGGUAAAAACAUAUAAAAUUUACCAUCUUAAUCACUUUGAGUGUACAGUUCAUCAGUGUUAACUGUAUUCACCUUGUGCAACAGAUCUCAAGGACUUUUUCACCUUGUAAAACUAAGAUUCUCUAUUUAUUGAACAAAUCCCCAUUUCCUCCUUCCCCAAGUCUCUCUCAACUGAAAUUAUAAUUUUUUGUUUCUAUGAGUUUGAAUACUUUAGAUACCUUGUUGCCAUGGUUUGAAUGUGCCCCCCAGAUUUCAUGUGUGUGAAACUUAAUCUCCAAAUUUGUAUGUUGAUGGCAUUUGGAAGUGGUGGGGACUUUGUUUAUUUAUUUAUUUUUAAUUUUUUAAUUUUAUAUUAUUAUUAUUAUUAUUAUACUUUAAGGUUUAGGGUACAUGUGCACAAUGUGCAGGUUAGUUACAUAUGUAUACAUGUGCCAUGCUGGUGUGCUGCACCCAUUAACUCGUCAUUUAUCAUUAGGUAUAUCUCCUAAAGCUAUCCCUCCCCCCUCCCCCCACCCCACAACAGUCCCCAGAGUGUGAUGAUCCCCUUCCUGUGUCCAUGUGUUCUCAUUGUUCAGUUCCCACCUAUGAGUGAGAAUAUGCAGUGUUUGGUUUUUUGUUCUUGCGAUAGUUUACUGAGAAUGAUGAUUUCCAGCUUCAUCCAUGUCCCUACAAAGGACAUGAACUCAUCAUUUUUUAUGGCUGCAUAGUAUUCCAUGGUGUAUAUGUGCCACAUUUUCUUAAUCCAGUCUAUUGUUGUUGGACAUUUGGGUUGGUUCCAAGUCUUUGCUAUUGUGAAUAGUGCUGCAAUAAACAUACGUGUGCAUGUGUCUUUA